AGUUCUGCCACCGUCACUGAGAAGCUCAGCGGUAGCUUUUGGGAAGCAGGACGUUCUCACCAGGAGAGCGUCCUCUCGAGAUUUCUGCUCCCUCCAUUCAGGGCGUUUGGGAGCCACCCCUUCAUUUUUUAAAAAAAGUAUUUCUCUGUGACCGACGGCCGGGGCCUUCUGACGGUCUGAGGUCUUGCUUGGGCCAGUCACCUCCUGUCACGGUCCGCGGAGGGGGGAAGGAUAAGAGGGCGAGGAGCUCAUCGCUCGCCACCCCCGUGGGCUUCUUGGGCGCAGGUCGGAGCUGGGUGGGCCGGCUCCCCGGCCCCUGGCUUGGGCGACCAUGUCCGCAUCCGCCCAGCAGCUGGCGGAGGAGCUGCAGAUCUUCGGCCUAGACUGCGAGGAGGCUCUAAUUGAGAAAUUGGUAGAGCUUUGUGUUCAGUAUGGACAGAAUGAGGAGGGAAUGGUAGGCGAGCUUAUAGCCUUCUGCACCAGCACACAUAAAGUUGGCCUUACCUCAGAGAUCCUGAACUCUUUUGAGCAUGAGUUUCUGAGCAAAAGAUUAUCGAAAGCCAGGCAUAGUACCUGCAAGGACAGUGGCCAUGCAGGAGCUAGAGACAUUGUUUCCAUUCAAGAGCUAAUUGAAGUGGAAGAAGAAGAGGAAAUCCUCUUGAACUCUUACACCACACCUUCAAAGGGUUCUCAGAAGCGAGCUAUCUCUACCCCAGAAACCCCCCUAACAAAAAGGAGUGUGUCAACUCGUAGCCCCCAUCAGCUACUCUCACCGUCAAGUUUCUCUCCAAGUGCUACUCCCUCCCAGAAAUACAACUCACGAAGUAACCGAGGAGAAGUGGUUACCUCCUUCGGCUUAGCACAGGGAGUAUCUUGGUCUGGGAGAGGAGGAGCUGGAAACAUCAGCCUGAAGGUCUUGGGAUGUCCAGAGGCACUAACUGGGAGCUACAAAUCCAUGUUUCAGAAGCUCCCAGACAUUCGAGAAGUUCUGACCUGUAAGAUAGAAGAACUUGGCAGCGAACUCAAGGAACAUUACAAGAUUGAAGCUUUCACUCCUUUGCUAGCCCCAGCACAGGAGCCUGUCACUCUGCUGGGCCAGAUUGGCUGUGAUAGCAACGGGAAGCUGAACAACAAGUCAGUGAUUCUCGAGGGAGACCGGGAACAUUCCUCGGGUGCUCAAAUUCCAGUGGAUUUAUCUGAGCUUAAGGAAUAUUCUCUGUUUCCUGGACAGGUUGUAAUUAUGGAAGGAAUCAACACCACUGGUAGGAAACUUGUUGCCACCAAACUCUACGAGGGUGUGCCACUUCCAUUUUAUCAGCCCACUGAAGAGGAUGCAGACUUUGAGCAAAGCAUGGUCCUGGUUGCCUGUGGACCAUACACCACAUCUGACAGCAUCACGUAUGACCCCCUGCUUGACCUGAUUGCUGUCAUCAACCAUGACCGGCCAGAUGUCUGCAUCCUGUUUGGCCCUUUCCUGGAUGCUAAGCAUGAACAGGUGGAGAAUUGUCUACUGACAAGUCCAUUUGAAGACAUUUUCAAGCAGUGUCUACGAACAAUUAUUGAAGGCACAAGAAGCUCCGGCUCCCACCUUGUCUUUGUCCCGUCAUUGAGAGAUGUGCACCAUGAGCCUGUGUACCCCCAGCCGCCUUUCAGCUACUCCGAUCUGUCUCGAGAGGACAAAAAGCAAGUACAGUUUGUGUCCGAGCCCUGCAGCCUCUCCAUAAACGGAGUGAUCUUCGGCUUGACAUCCACAGAUCUGCUUUUCCACCUGGGGGCCGAGGAGAUCAGUAGUUCUUCCGGAACUUCAGACAGAUUCAGCCGAAUACUCAAGCACAUCUUGACCCAGAGGAGCUACUACCCACUCUACCCGCCCCAAGAAGACAUGGCCAUUGACUAUGAGUCGUUCUAUGUUUACGCACAGCUGCCUGUCACCCCAGAUGUCCUCAUCAUCCCGUCAGAGCUGAGGUACUUCGUGAAGGAUGUCCUCGGCUGUGUCUGUGUGAACCCUGGGCGCCUUACCAAAGGGCAGGUGGGAGGCACCUUCGCCCGACUCUACCUUAGGAGGCCGGCAGCGGACGGGGCAGAGAGGCAGAGCCCAUGCAUUGCUGUGCAGGUCGUCAGGAUCUGAGGCUUCUGUCCUCUGCUGUUCUCUGCUGUGUGGGCCCUUAAAGUCUUAGCCAAGAGCCAAGACAUAGCCCUGUGACAAGGUGAACAGUUGGGUGGGAAAGGAGAGAGGAGCCAGCCAGGGAGGGGCAGCUGCAGUGACCAGGCCCAGCAGGGAGGACUUGUGCAGCCGGGCCUGCCUCUGAGUGGUGCCUCUCCUGGAAGGAAGCUCUUGCUUCUCAGUCCAUGCUCCGUGUCCAGAAGUAAGCCAGCUGUGGAUCCCGCCCACUCAGAAAAGGCGAGAAGGCUUUGUGAUUUUCUACAUGAAUCAAACACAGAAACAACUUUUGGAGAAAUUAAAUUCUGAGUGUGACUUCUGAGUUUGACCUUUCUUCUAUUUUCUUUUAUUUAUUUAUUUUGUUUUUAGACGGAGUCUCGAUCUGUCGCCCAGGCUGGAGUGCAGUGGUGAGAUCUCGGCUCACUGCAAGCUCUGCCGCCCGGGUUCAUGCCAUUCUCCUGCCUCAGCCUCCUGAGUAGCUGGGACUACAGGCACCCACCACCACGCCUGGCUAAUUUUUUGUAUUUUUAGUGGAGAUGGGGUUUCACCAUGUUAGCCAGGAUGGUCUCGAUCUCCUGACCUUGUGAUCUGUCCGCCUCAGCCUCCCAAAGUGCUGGGAUUACAGGCGUGAGCCACCGCGCCCGGCCCCUUUCUUCUAUUUUCUUUAUCCUGGUAGUAGACAAAGAAUGUUGCCUAUUUGACCUAUGUCCAGAGAAGGCAGAGUGUCAGUCACACUGGGUUUCUAUCCAGCCCCAGUCCUGUCCAGUGGGUAACUCUCAGCCCCACUCCUCAUCCCCCAAAGGCCCCAGUGACCUCUAUGCUGCAGAGGUGCACUGGGUGGGCCCUAGAGCUGGGCUGCAGAGCAAGCAACUGGCUGCAUGCCUGGGCCUCCCUGCGCAGUUCCUCACAUGCAUGCUGUGGUCCCAGCCUGACCUCUCCAUCUGGAGGGGGCCGCCUCGCUGGGCUGUUCCAAAGCUGGAGUCCUGGUGGCAGCUGCUUUGCCAAGUCGCGCAGUAGCCAGGGCUUGCCUGCAGCCCAGAACACUCAGACAGGGUCAGGCCUUCCAGGGUUCACAGCACGUCCCAUGCCCCUAUGUCCUGGCAUCUGGGGAAAAGCUGUCACUGGCCAGACGUGGAGUGGCUUCCUGCCCUAAGCUGGCAGGCUGUCCUGCCUCACAUGCCAGAGCCAAGACCGGCAAACCCCAGCUGUCAGGGCAGGGAAGUGGGCAAGGGGGCAGCAAGCUGCUGGUGUCUAUGCCUUGACUCCGAGAUAAAUAGAUGACCUAACAGUGGCCAACUUUUGCCUCUCACCUUUCUGACGGUGAAAUGGAAUCGAGCCCCAGACCUGACCAGGGUACAGUAAAAGGUCUUCCUUUAAACACAA